GUGGCGGCGCGCGCAGCGGCAGGCGGCGGCGGGAUGGAGCCCGAGCCCGAGCCCGCGGCCGUGGAGGUUCCCGCGGGGCGCGUGCUCAGCGCCCGGGAGCUCUUCGCCGCCCGCUCGCGGUCGCAGAAGCUGCCCCAGCGCUCGCAUGGCCCCAAGGACUUUCUGCCCGACGGCUCGGCAGCUCAGGCCGAGCGGCUGCGCCGGUGCCGGGAAGAGCUCUGGCAGCUGCUGGCAGAGCAGCGCGUGGAGCGCCUGGGCAGCUUGGUGGCUGCCGAGUGGAGGCCAGAAGAGGGCUUCGUGGAGUUGAAGUCUCCCGCGGGCAAAUUCUGGCAGACCAUGGGCUUCUCAGAGCAGGGCCGGCAGCGCCUUCACCCGGAAGAGGCCUUGUAUCUUCUGGAGUGUGGCUCCAUCCACCUCUUCCACCAAGACCUGCCACUGUCUAUCCAGGAAGCUUACCAGCUGCUGCUGACCGACCACACUGUGACCUUCCUGCAGUACCAGGUCUUCAGCCACCUGAAGAGGUUGGGUUAUGUGGUUCGACGAUUCCAACCAAGCUCUGUCCUGUCCCCGUAUGAGAGGCAGCUUAACCUGGAUGCCAGCGUGCAGCACUUGGAGGAUGGAGAUGGCAAGAGAAAGAGGAGCAGCUCCAGCCCUCGGUCCAUUAAUAAGAAGGCCAAGGCCCUGGACAACUCCCUGCAACCCAAGAGUCUGGCAGCCUCCAGCCCACCUCCCUGCAGCCAGCCCAGCCAAUGCCCAGAGGAGAAACCCCAGGAGUCAAGCCCCAUGAAGGGCCCAGGGGGCCCCUUUCAGCUUCUGGGGUCCCUGGGCCCCAGCCCUGGCCCGGCCAGGGAGGGGGUGGGGUGCAGCUGGGAGAGUGGCAGAGCCGAGAACGGAGUCACGGGAGCCGGUAAGCGGCGCUGGAACUUCGAGCAGAUCUCCUUCCCCAACAUGGCUUCAGACAGCCGCCACACCCUUCUGCGCGCCCCAGCCCCAGAGCUGCUCCCGGCCAACGUGGCUGGGCGGGAGACAGACGCUGAGUCCUGGUGCCAGAAGCUGAACCAGCGCAAGGAGAAGCUCUCCAGGCGGGAACGGGAGCACCACGCGGAGGCCGCGCAGUUCCAGGAAGAUGUCAACGCCGAUCCCGAGGUGCAGCGGUGCUCCAGCUGGCGGGAGUACAAGGAGCUGCUGCAGCGGCGGCAGGUGCAGAGGAGCCAGCGCCGGGCCCCUCACCUGUGGGGCCAGCCCGUCACCCCGCUGCUGAGUCCUGGCCAGGCCAGCUCCCCAGCCGUGGUCCUUCAGCAUAUCUCUGUGCUGCAGACAACACACCUUCCUGAUGGAGGUGCCCGGCUGUUGGAGAAGUCUGGGGGCUUGGAAAUCAUCUUUGAUGUUUACCAGGCCGACGCUGUGGCCACAUUCCGAAAGAAUAACCCUGGCAAACCCUAUGCCCGGAUGUGCAUUAGUGGAUUUGAUGAGCCUGUCCCAGACCUCUGCAGCCUCAAGCGGUUGUCUUACCAGAGUGGGGAUGUCCCUCUGAUCUUUGCCCUGGUGGAUCAUGGUGACAUCUCCUUCUACAGCUUCAGGGACUUCACGUUGCCCCAGGAUGUGGGGCACUGACCUCACAGCUCUGCAGAGGAUGGAGCUUGCUCCGGGGGACCGGGACUGUCUGUUCUCAGGGACCAUCUCGGCUGCCUCCUGUACCCAGACUCUAACCUGUAGCUUCAGAGGCCAGUCUGGGCCUUGGCCCUGGGUGUCUGAUACUCACAGAGUGAAACUGUGACCCUCUCCCUUCCCUGCUGCCUUGCAGUGACCCCUCUGGAACUCAGGACUCGAUUUUAAGGACCCAGGAGGUGGGGCAGAAGAGAGGACUGUGUGCCUUUAACGAGAGGGUGCCUGCUUCGUGCUAUAAAGCCAAAGCCAUUAAAAAUAGAUUUCUUUUC